AUCUCCGCUGGUUCCCGGAAGCCGCCGCGGACAAGCUCUCCCGGGCGCGGGCGGGGGUCGUGUGCUUGGAGGAAGCCGCGGAACCCCCAGCGUCCGUCCAUGGCGUGGAGCCUUGGGAGCUGGCUGGGUGGCUGCCUGCUGGUGUCAGCAUUGGGAAUGGUACCACCUCCCGAAAAUGUCAGAAUGAAUUCUGUUAAUUUCAAGAACAUUCUACAGUGGGAGUCACCUGCUUUUGCCAAAGGGAACCUGACUUUCACAGCUCAGUACCUAAGUUAUAGGAUAUUCCAAGAUAAAUGCAUGAAUACUACCUUGACGGAAUGUGAUUUCUCAAGUCUUUCCAAGUAUGGUGACCACACCUUGAGAGUCAGGGCUGAAUUUGCAGAUGAGCAUUCAGACUGGGUAAACAUCACCUUCUGUCCUGUGGAUGACACCAUUAUUGGACCCCCUGGAAUGCAAGUAGAAGUACUUGCUGAUUCUUUACAUAUGCGUUUCUUAGCCCCUAAAAUUGAGAAUGAAUACGAAACUUGGACUAUGAAGAAUGUGUAUAACUCAUGGACUUAUAAUGUGCAAUACUGGAAAAACGGUACUGAUGAAAAGUUUCAAAUUACUCCCCAGUAUGACUUUGAGGUCCUCAGAAACCUGGAGCCAUGGACAACUUAUUGUGUUCAAGUUCGAGGGUUUCUUCCUGAUCGGAACAAAGCUGGGGAAUGGAGUGAGCCUGUCUGUGAGCAAACAACCCAUGACGAAACGGUCCCCUCCUGGAUGGUGGCCGUCAUCCUCAUGGCCUCGGUCUUCAUGGUCUGCCUGGCACUCCUCGGCUGCUUCGCCUUGCUGUGGUGCGUUUACAAGAAGACAAAGUACGCCUUCUCCCCUAGGAAUUCUCUUCCACAGCACCUGAAAGAGGAGUAGAAAAGUACCCCAUUGCAGUAGAGAUAAGUGGAUCUGAAACCCCAACAGCAGCUGAAGAGGUUCUUUAUGACAGCUGGAACCUGCACUCCAGUUGCCCUUGCACGUUUGUGGUUUAGCAGUCCCAGAGACAAAUCUGCCACUUCUGGCUUGCAUCCAACAAAAGUGCAGCUGUUCAUCAUUAGGAGAUGUUGGCUGAUGUACAUAGACAUGUAAGAAAGAUUCAAAGCGUCAUGGAUGGAUCACCAAUAACACCAGCAUAUGCAAGACCAGAGGAGAGUGUGUGAUCCAGGUCCUAGGAUUGACAAAUGAGGACUCAGUCCCUACUUGGGUUGGUGUUUUAUUUUGACUUUUUUCUGAAACAGCAGAGAAGCUUACCAAAUAAUCACAAGGAGAUAAGAAAGUGUUUACAUUUGUUUCAGUUGCUCUUCACUGCCUCCUUAUGACCAACACUCACAAUUCUAUGGUCUUAGCAGUUGCACUAAGAAGUCAGAAGAACCUGCUAUUGUGGGUUCAUAAUCUUUUAUUACCUUUCACUGAGAAACAAUUUAUACUACUAAACAAGAUAUCAGUUAUGAUGCUCAAGAUUUUAAGUGCCUUUUGAACUAAAAACAAACAAAAAAAUUGUGACCUGCAUAUAAUGUAAAUGGUUUAUCUUCAAGUCAAAAGCCACAGGUUUACCUCUGCAGCUUUACUCUUUCCUAAACAUUGCUUUCGUGUAUUGCUUAUGCAUGCUUUCUGCGUCCCAAAAAGUAUGUAGAGAAUAACAGUUUAAGUCCUCCAGAGGAGUUACUACCUCUACUACAUGUUUCAUUCUCAUUACAUGUUGCAUUGCUUAUUAAUAUCUGUGUUUUGUAGUGGACUUCAUGAGGACAGGUAAUGUUACCAACUGAAUUGUGUACCCCCAAAAUUCACAUGUUGAAACCCUAAUCCCCAAUGUGACUGUAUUUGAAGUAGGGCCUACAGCAGGUAAUUAAGGUUAAAUGAGGUCAUAAGUGUGGGGCCCUGAAUCGAUGAGAUUAGUGUCCUUAUAAGAAGAAACAGCAGAGACCUUGUUCUCUCCACCAUAUGAGGACACAGUGAGAAUGUAGCCAUCUGUGAGCAGGAAGGGAGGCCUCACCAGGAUCCAAAUGAGCCAGAACCUUAAUCUUGGACUUCUCACCCUGCAGAACUGUGAGAAAAUAAAUUUCUGUUGUUUAAGCCA